CGCUCCGGUGUGCGGGCUGGAGGGAACACUGGCUGCUCGAGUUCUCCCAGUAAGCCUCCGAGAGCUUUGAAGGCAGUGCGGUCCUUCAGCGGAUGGUGUUACCUGAUACCGCUGCUAAAAGUGGCAAUUUAAUCUGAGUGUCCCUCAAAUUUGAUAUGCGGCAGAUCACGUUUCUCCUGUGGUUUCUCUGAGGGUGACAGUAUUACUUUACUUUGCAGUUAUUAAGAUUCAGUUUUUAAACGUGACUUUUCACUUGUAUUUGUAAAGCGUUAACUAGGCCUAGCACCUUCUGUUUCUAAUAGAGUUAAAGCCAGUGAAGCCUCUCUCGGCCGUGCUGGUGGGAGUAGGGUGAGGGCUCACUUCUCGCUGCAGAGAUUAAGCCUUCUUGUUCUGAAUUCAUUACAAAGGGAUGUAAAAUAAGCCAGUUUGAAAUGUGAACCCAUUAAUACUGUUUGGGGAUUAGUUCUAAAUUCCAAUGAAUUAAAGUUAGAAUAUCAUCUCCCAAAAUGGUUCAGCUUGGAGAGUUGCCCAUACACAAAUGUGUUCUAAGAAAAUGACAUAAACUUGAUUGGACGAGAUUGGAGACAAAGCUUCUUAAAAUACCUUUAAGUAGCAAAUUGAUUUUAGGAUCAAGCUUUUGCAUGAAUUUCAGGGAAAUGGCAGGUGCACAGACAUGCAGUCCAGCUUUCCUACGAGGCAUUUGCUCUUCAAAACCCCGUGGGUGCUGUUUAUCAUGGCAGAAUUAAAAUCUGAGGGCUGCAGCUAAGUCAAUGAAAUCUCACUUAUGCGUUCACUCCACCAUUCUGUUCAUCUGCCAUGGACGUGCCCAGUUUAGUUCUGUGCUCACAGCAGAGGAAUGCCAUCGAGCCUGUGGCCGGUCCCUAAAUAACGGGAGAGCUGAAGCGCCGGCGAUAAGAUAAGGCUCCCGGCUUGCUGGAGACGGGGAGGCGUCCGACUGUUCACAGCCUUGGCGUCCAGGAGCUCCUGCUUCUGGUUUUCCAGGCGGCCACUCGUGUGCCCUUAGGACCAGCAACCCCAUGCUUGUGCCCCGCAGCCCAGAACAGGUGCACCCCACACACAGACACCUGUGGGACACAGCUCCGGCUUGUUUUCACCGUAGACGGCUGGAGCUCACUCUUGAGUUUGGCUUCCUCUGGGCGUCUGAUGCCGUGUGUGCGCUCAUACCAGCUCUGCAUGUCCCAUUUCUGGUAGCACUUGGUGGGCGUUUUGUAAAUGGCAGCGUCCAUGGCUGUGGGUCUGGUCCUGCCAGGCCCGCAGGGAGGGCAGCGGCACAGGACACUCCAAAAGUGCACCGACGGAGAUCGGCCCAACAGGACACGAAAUUCACACAGUUAAAAGGGUUACGGACGUUUAGGGCACUGUUUUUUGUUUGUUUUUUGAGACGGAGUCUUUCUCCAUCGCCCAGGCUGGAGUGCAGUGGCGUGAUCUCAGCUCACUGCAACCUCCACCUCCCAGGUUCAAGUGAUUCUCCUGCCUCAGCCUCCUGAGUAGCUGGGGCUACAGGUGCCCACCACCACGCCCGGCUGAUUUUUGUAUUUUUAGUAGAGACGGGGUUUCACCACGUUGUCCAGGCUGGUCUCGAACUCCUGACCUCAAGUGAUCCACCCACCUCAGCUUCCCAAAGUGCUGGGAUGACAGGCGUGAGCCACCAUGGGGCGCUAUUCUUAAGGAGGAAGUAAGUUUGCUCUAAGCUCUCAGGGUCCUCAGCUGUGGACUGGAAGGGAGGGUUCACUGUGCUGCUGCAGCGUCUAGUUUGUGGGUCAUGAGAAAAUACGCAUCCAAGAUCACCCCUGGAAUUGCUUACUGUGGGCGGCAAGCCACCCAGGCACUGAGGCAAGAGACAGAGGACACGAGCUGUUCCAGUAUAAUAAAACAAGAAUAGUUAUACCAGAUAUAGAUCUUAGAUAUGAUUAUAUAUGAAUAUCAUUAAUCAUUAGUUUGUAGCAAUUACUUUUUAUUCCAAUAUUAUGAUAAUCCUCGCUCUAUAAUCAUAGCCUAGGAAAAACCAGGCCAUACAGAGAUAGGAGCUGAGGGGACAUAGUGAGGUGUGACCAGAAGACAAGAGUGCGAGCCUUCUGUUAUGCCCGGACAGGGCCACCAGAUGGCUCCUUGGUCUAGCUGUGACGCCAGCGUCUGGGAAGACGCCCGUUACCAGGCGGAUCGUGGUCCAGCAGUAGCAAAAGGUGGCAAGGAACAACACCUGCUACUUAGCAGACCAGGAAGGGGGGGGGGGUCUCCCUUUCCCCAGGGGAGUUUAGAGAAGACUGCUCUUCCACCUCUUGUGGAGGGCCUGACAUGAGUCAGGCUCGCCCGCAGUUAUCCGGAGGCCUAACCGUCUCCCUGUGAUGCUGUGCUUCAGUGGUCACACUCCUAGUCUGCCUUCAUGUUCCAUCCUGUACACCUGGCUCUGCCUUCUAGAUAGCAGUAGUAAAUUAGUGAAAAAUUAGUACUAUCAGUACUAAUAGUCCCUGAUAUGCAGAAAUAAUGGCAUAAGCUGUCUUUCUCUCUGUCUCCUCUCCCUCUCUGCCUCGGCUGCCAGGCAGGGAAGGGCCCCCUGUCCAGUGGACACGUGACCCACAUGACCUUACCUACCAUUGGAGGUGACUCGCAUUCUUUACCCUGCCCCUUCUGCCUUGUAUCCAAUAAAUAACAGUGCAGCCAGACAUUCGGGGCCACUACCGGUCUCCGUGCAUUGGUAGUAGUGGUCCCCCGGGCCCAGCUGCCUUUUCUCUUAUCUCUUGUCUUGUGUCUUUAUUUCUACACUCUCUCGUCACUGCACACAGGGAGAGACCCACCGACCCUGUGGGGCUGGUCCCUACAGCUUACCCCUCUAGAAACCAAAGCAAGCAGAUUUUUUUCAACUCACUAAAAAUCAAAGUCGAAAUUUCACUUAAGUUUAUCUUUGUUCUUUAAAUAACAAAUUGUAGCCUAUGGAAGGGGGUCUUUAAGCUGUGUUAACAAUGGUGAGGGCUGGGCACAGUGGCUCACGUCUGCAAUCCCAGCAUUGUGGGAGGCCACGGUGGGCAGAUUGCCUGAGCCCAGGAGUUCUAGAUCAGCCUAGGAAACAUAGCAAGACUCCAUCUCUACAAAACGACAAUGGUGAGUGCUGACUCCACAGCACUUCUGUACCAGGCAUUGUUCCAGCUGCUUCACGCAUGUUAUCCUCCACACAUGCUCCUCACAUCACCGUGGAGGCUGAUUUUAUCACAAUCUUACAGGAGAAAAAAUUGACAUACAGAGAGGUUCAGGCGCUUGCCCAGUGCCACACAGCCCAGCGAGUGGCAGAGCUUGGACGGGAACCAGAGAAUCUGGCCCCUGUGCUCGUAAGCAUCCUCCCUGACUGCUGAGAUCACGGUGGCCUGCAGGUAUCCUAACAAUUGCAGUGUGCAGGGGCUCUUCAGCAUGCUUUCCAAAGACAGGCAGACUUUUACAAAUGGAACUACGUUUGGCAGCUUUAAGUAAGCUGCACUGAAAAGUCCUUCACCCCACGAGCCACGGGGCUGUGUGGUCUGGCAAACCCUGGCUCUGCUGCUAGAGUGAGCACAGGUCUGAGGGUCGGGGCAGCCUGUGUGGCUCCCUCCUUCCGGGUGAGCCUCUCUGAACCGGGCUGCCUCCUUCCGGGUGUGUCUCUCUGAACGGGGCUCCCUCCUUCCGGGUGAGCCUCUGAACAGGGCUGUCUCCUUCUGGGUGAGCCUCUCUGAACCGGGCUGCCUCCUUCCGGGUGUGUCUCUCUGAACGGGGCUCACUCCUUCCAGACUACUGGUGCCUGGAUGAUCUGUACCGGGAGAUGGUGAGAUGCUAUGUGGAAAUCGUUGAGAAGCUUCCAGAACGCCGGCCAGACCCAGCUACCAUUGAAGGCUGUGCUCAGCUAAAGCCCAAUAACUACCUUCUCGCCUGGCACACACCGUUCAAUGAAAAAGGCUCAGGGUUUGGAGCGGCCACCAAGGCCAUGUGCAUCGGCCUGCGGUACUGGAAGCCUGAGCGGCUGGAGACCCUCAUCGAGGUCAGCGUGGAGUGCGGCCGGAUGACCCACAACCAUCCCACAGGCUUCCUGGGCUCCCUGUGCACGGCCCUGUUUGUGUCGUUCGCCGCACAAGGAAAGCCCCUGGUCCAGUGGGGGAGAGACAUGCUGCGGGCGGUGCCUCUGGCAGAAGAGUACUGCAGGAAGACCAUCCGGCACACGGCAGAAUACCAGGAGCACUGGUUUUACUUUGAAGCUAAAUGGCAAUUUUAUUUGGAGGAGAGGAAAAUCAGUAAAGACUCAGAAAAUAAAGCCAUCUUCCCCGACAAUUAUGAUGCAGAAGAGAGGGAAAAGACCUACAGGAAGUGGAGCUCGGAAGGUCGAGGGGGAAGACGAGGCCACGAUGCCCCCAUGAUAGCCUAUGACGCCCUCCUUGCAGCAGGAAACAGCUGGACUGAGCUGUGUCACCGGGCCAUGUUUCAUGGAGGGGAGAGCGCGGCCACGGGCACCAUUGCAGGCUGCCUGUUCGGGUUGCUGUACGGCCUGGACCUCGUUCCCAAAGGCUUGUACCAGGACCUGGAGGACAAGGAGAAGCUGGAGGACCUGGGCGCGGCUCUCUACCGCCUGUCCACAGAGGAGAACCGGAAGAGCAGCAAGACCUGCAGUGACGUCAUGUCUGUGGACGCCCAAACCCUGAAGAAGAAGAUGGGCAAGCUGGCCUGUGACCCGGCCGCCCACUCCAUCCUCAGCAGCCUGCUGCUCUACGUCACGGGCCGCGCAGACCGGCCCCCGGGGACAGAGGCCGGGGGGAGCAGGCCCAGCCACCAGCCCCAGACCCAGGAGGCCACCCAGCGGCCCACGCGCUUCCAGCUCCUGCAGGCCAAGUUCCUGGGCACUGGCCGGGAGCGCUACCUCAAGAGGACCAGGGAGGUGGGCCGGCUGAUCUCCAAGGACAAGCAGGGGCCGGGUGGGGGCCUCGUGGGUGCCACCAUCAACAAGCUCCUGGAGAAGACCAAGGAGCCGGCCCCAAAGCCCUGCCUCAGCGAGAAGCCCCGCUGGGGCCACCCGGCCGGGAAGAGCACCGUGAAAAACAUCCUGAAGAUAUUCUUGGCCGCCGAGGAGAAGGAGGCGAAGGAGAAAGAAGCACGCGAGAAGCCCCCUGUGGAGCGGCCCAAAGCCGCCAGGGGCCUCUUGCCGAAGAUCAUGGGCAAGAGCUCGGUGCUGUCCAAGCUGCGGGAGAAGUUCGAGCAGAACAGCUGCCUGUGCUCCGAGGCCAGUGCGCUGAGGCUGCACACGCAGGAGCGGAAGAAGAGGAACCUGCAGAGGAAGAGGAUGCACCGGCCGGAGGUGCGCGUGCUGCACACGGCCACCAUGGCCAGCACCUGCGUCAAGAUGCCCCCUGCCCGCUUUCUGGCCUGCACGGCUGAGCCCCUGCCGGCCCUCAGCAUCGCCACCGUCGUCUGUGGCCCCAGGAGCUGGCUGUCCCACUGCACCAAAAUCAGCCACUCGGAGGCAAGGCGUCCACCCAGAGGAGAAGCCAGCGUGCCCCCUAGUGCCAGGGAGACGGGGCCCAGUGGGAACAAAGCAGUGGGAAAGGGGCCCCUGGAGGAGGAGCCCCAAAGACAGCCAAGGCCCUCGAAGCCCGUGACACCCCAGGUGAUGGCUCAGAGGGACGGCCACGCUGUCCCCUCGCUGGCCUUCUCUUGUGCUCCCUGCACAGGUGGAGUCCUUCCUGGCCUUGUGCCUGCAUCAUCCCCACUGGGACCGGCCAGCCCUUGGGGCACCGGAUCAGCCGGAGGUGAUGGGACUGCAGACCCCACCGCAGAGAGCACCGCAGGAGGCGUCCAGGAGGUGAGGGGAGCCAGGCUCACGUGGCCUCCUGGGCCCCCAGGCGAGUGUGCAGGGGAGGGCCCUGAAAUCACCAUGACUGUUUGCAGUUCAGAGGAUGAAAGGGAAGGAGCAGGCUUCCCAGACCCAGGGAGAGACCCCCUCUUUGCCACCCAGAAGUAUUUCCCAGAACAGAAGGUGCCGGAGCACAUCCCACCCCUGAACGCUCCAUCGGUCCAGGCUGCUCGGAGAACACAGCCUGCCACGGAGCCUCCACGGAUAACUGUCCAAAUUCCAGUUGUCCAUGAAAUGCCAGCCCCUCCCACCAGGCUGCAAAAUAUGUCAAGUGGUGAAAACAAACCUUGUAUUUGUGGAGGAGAGAAUGUGGUUGAAAAUGCCCACACAGAAUUUCCCACCGUGACUGAGAACAGAAGGGGUCACCGAGCCCCAGUGGAACUGAGCAAGCUUUCAGGGAUGCAGGCGGGACUCAGCGCCUCUUCGCCGCAGGGGCCACGGGCAGCUCCGCGUCUGGCAGCAGCAAGAGGGGCUGUGGGCGCCGACCACAGUGUCCCAGAGACACUUCUGACACAGAGACUCCAGACAGAUCCUGCUGGCGGGAAGGAAAACAAAGGCAGCUUUGAGAAUUCACACGGUCCCAGGAAUCCUGACGAUAUUUCAGGAGAGAGGACCUCUGAGCUCAGAGAUGUGAAGCAUCCGUUGCCGGAAUCUAAUGAAAUAUCAAUGCAGAAGAAGGGCUCCGCAACAAAUGAUCCUGCAGCCUCACAAAACCUUCUGAGGGGAAACACCAGCCAUGCCUCCAGCAGCCAGCAAGUGCCGUCCCCGACUGGGAGAAACCCAACAGGAGCCCCCACGUCACUGGCGGCAUCAUCCAAGGGGCGUACGGGGCCUGAGGGUGUCACCCCGAUGGGCAUGACAGUGCCCGGUGCGCUGGAGGAAUGCAGAAGGCCGCUGCUAAUAGAGUCUUCUCAGCCCCUGAAGGCUGCCGAGGAAAUCACCAGCCAUGAUGUUCGCGAGAACCCACUGUCCUCAUUAAAUGAACCACCCAAACCAGGUAUGAAAGCCUGUGGGGCGAUGGCAGCUGCAGGGAGCGUUGCGAGCCGCGCCACGCCUGCACCAGCGCCAGGCAGCACCCAGAGCCCUGGAGACCGCACAGCGGGAGAGCCAGAGACGCUGGGCCAGUGGGGAAGCAGAGCCUUGUCCGAAAGCCACCCCAGAGGAGAGGCUCUCCCUCGAGACCCUCACAGCCACGGCCUCCUGGCCCCUGGGGGAUCCUUGGAGCCCAAGAGUGGAGCAGCAGGGAGGAGCCUCCUGAGAGGCGUGGCCCUCGUCCAGCACCCAGAGGACAUUGCGACCCUCGCCCGCCACCCGGAGGAUGCUGCGGCCCUCGCCCGGCACCCAGAGGCGGCCCGAUUAUACAUUUCAAACACAUCAGCAGCCAGCAGACAUACAGCAGCUGUAGGAGGCAGAAAGGAUGUGGCUGUGGAAGGAAACCUUUUGGGUUUCAGCACAGAGUCUGGAAUUCCUGCUUCUGAUCAUCCUAGGCCACAGGCAAGGAGCGUGGCAGAGUCCCCCAGCUAUGGCCCUGGCCUCCCGCCGUCGCCUCCUGAGAACCCACAGGCAAAGGGCAGGGAGGGCGUCAGGUUUCCCCGUGGGGCGGAGCCUGACCAUCUGCUUCCCGCAGUGCCUCCCGCGGAGGUGGACAUGGGGUGGGUAGGUGGCACCCACCAGCGGGGCCCUCCCCAUCUACAGGCACACCUGCCCCCUACUGCUGGUGACACACAGGCAAAGCUCCGGGCCAGUGUCCCCGAGCCUAGGACGCAGGCAGGUGAAUCCCAGGAGCGUCCCCUGACACAGGCGGACCUGGGGAGGCAACAGAGUCACCAGGCACAGGAGGAGACCCCCCAGCCCGGGGAUGCGGGGAAGAGGGUGGCGCCGUCGGGCUCGAAGGUUGUGCUGAACCCAGCAAAAGAGCCUCAGACAUGGUGGGCACAGGAUCUGGCCGGGGACAAAGGGAUGGCCAUUGGGGUUGGGGGCGCCUGCCAGCGCAGUGACCAAGGUCAGCAGCAUCUGCAGGGACCCUGGGAGGAGCGGGGGCGGAGCACGGCGUGGGGAGAGGGCACCAGGGCUGCCAGGAACCCAGCUGUGCCUCCAGGGGAGCCCGAGGGGCCGGGAAGCCCGGCAGCCCAAGGACAGGCCCAGAAACAGGUUCAGGAAUGGGACCGGGGACAGGUUCAGGGACACGCUCAAGAACAGGCCCAGUGGCAGACCCAGAUAGAGGCCCAGGGGCAGGCACAGGAACAGGCUCAGGGUGGGACCCAGGGACACAGUCAGGGACAGGCCCAGAAACAGUUUCAGAAUUGGGCCCAGGGACAGGCUCAGGGACACGCUCAAGAACAGGCCCAGUGGCAGACCCAGAUAGAGGCCCAGGGGCAGGCACAGGAACCAGCUCAGGGUGGGGCCCAGGGACAGGUUCAGGGACAGGCCCAGAAAUGGGCUCAGGGGCAGAUUCAGGGACAGGCCCAGAAACAGGUUCAAGGAGAGGUUCAGAAAUGGGCCCAGGAAGAGGCUCAGGGACAGGCCCAGUGGCAGACCCAGAUAAAGGCCCAGAAAUGGGCUCAGGAACAGACCCAGAAAGGGGCUCAGGAACGGGUUCAGGGUCAGGCCCAGAAAGGGGCUCAGGAACGGGCCCAGGAACAGGCUCAGGAGCAGACCCAGAUAGAGGCUCAGGGUCAGGCCCAGAAGGGGGCUCAGGAACGGGCUCGGGAACAGGCCCAGAAAGGGGCUCAGGAACGGGCUCGGGAACAGGCCCAGAAAGGGGCUCAGGAACGGGCUCGGGAACAGGCCCAGAAAGGGGCUCAGGAGCGGGCUCGGGAACAGGCCCAGAAAGGGGCUCAGGAACGGGCUCGGGAACAGGCCCAGAAAGGGGCUCAGGAACGGGCUCGGGAACAGGCCCAGAAAGGGGCUCAGGAACGGGCUCAGGAACAGGGUCGGGAGCAGACCCACAUAGAGGCUCAGGGUCAGGCCCAGAAAGGGGCUCAGGAAUGGGCUCGGGAUCGGGCUCGGGAUCAGGGCUGGGAGCAGACCCAGAUAGAGACUCAGAGGCAGACCCAGAAAGGGGCUCAGGAACGGGCUUGGGAACAGGGUCGGGAACAGGCCUUGACAAGUGGGAUGGCGCCUCGGGCCUGGGAGCAGCCCAUUAGUGGCAUAGCUGAGGGAGUGGAUGCUGCUGGCAGGAGUGGGGGGUCCAGAAGCCCAGCCCCCAGGGAUGGUGGACAGUCAGGGGGCAGUGGCCUGGGGGAGCCCAGCGCCGGGUACCCACCCCCAGGAAGCCGCCCCCUCAGGGGCAAGAGCAUUGCCACCUCUCCCCUGGGGCUGGGAAAGAGCCCAACUGAGCCCAAGCCUGAGGCUGGGGGCUGCGGGACUCCCCAGGCCCCGGCCCAGGAGGGGUCCCCAGACCACCCUGGGGCUGAGAGGGCCCUGCAGGACAGGAUGGAGGCAUCGGAGCCCGAGCGUCGCGGGAGGUCCAGGCACCUGGCCAAGUACAAAGCCCAGAGCUUCCGUGACCAGAGGGCCUUCGAUUUGUCCUUCAGACCAAUGAGCGUCAGGGCCAGCGACACGUCUGAGCUCCCAAAGUGAGGCCCCGAGUACACACCGUGGCUCGCCCAGCACUGUGACAUCCGCCCAUUGAGGGACUUCAGGCAUUUUCCUGCCUCCAAAUGCGUCUUGGAGCAUCCCCUACAGAGACGCCUGUUUCCAUAAUUUUCUUUCCCUUCUUCACAAGCUGACCUUGGGAGGAUUGAGCUACAUGUGGGUCGGGUUCCUGUCACCCCACAGAGCCACGAGGCCAUGGGGGUGGGAGGUGCGGGCCUGUGGCCUCACCAGGCCCUCGGGAUUCUUUGUGUCUUCACUCGGGGGCGCCGGCUCACCCCUCUCUCACACAGCCUGCAGCGUGGAGCUCACACCUCCCGCAGUGGCACGGUGUGUGCGUCCCCUUCGAUCUGCAGGAUGCUGGCACUUUGGGACACCUCCCCAGCUCUCACAGGGCCACCUCCCACUGCUCCCUGCCCACACCCCACCAUGCCCUGCUCUGACGUGGCCGCAUGGCACCCACCAUCCAUGGGCCCAAAGUGAUGCACACCGCCCCACCCCCAUGACUCGAAAGAAAGGGCAGAGCUUCCUCCAGCCUCAGACGCCCAGGUGGGUGCCGGGUGCUGUGUGGCUGCUGGGCCAUGUGGUGGUCACCAGAGGGUGUGGGGACGCUGGGAUCCCAGGCCGAAACCAGCUCAUCCGGAGGAAGAGGCCUCAGGAAAUGCCCACGUUAAGUUCUGAGAAAGGGACAGUGCAGAGCCGUGGGAAGCCAGGAUCCCAGGGAGGCUUCGUCUGGAAACUGGGUGCUGGGAGAACGAACGGGAGCCUGCCCGCCCUUCCCUGCAGUCCCUGUGGGUGGUGCCACUGGUGCCGGUGACCUGAGAGCCUCGCUGUCUGUCCUCCGUCCUCCCGAACAGCAUAGAAGUGUUUCCUGCCCUGGCCCGAGACGGCCCACGACUCCGGCCCUGUUCAGGUACUGAGGUAAUGCAUGUUCAGGCUGGAAUAUUUGAAUGCUGUCUAGAGGCACAAGAAGGAAAUCAAAGCCACCUGUGGUCACAUUGCCUCGAGAUGGUUUUUGUUGCUACUCUGGACUAUUUUUUAGGCUCUUCCUCCAUGCACCUAUUUUAAAGCACAUUCUUCCCCAUGAUGGAGCCAUGCACCUCCGUGUCGCGAUCCAUCGUCCCAGGCCACUCGGUGGCCUCUGAAACCCGGACCCGUGAGGCCACACGGCUGCCUGAGUGGCCCCGGAGCAGCUGGAUUUUCAGCGUGAACCGAUGCAGCCUGUCGCCCUACAGCCCCGCACCCUUGUUUUUGGUGGUGCCCUCCCUGUGGAAAGUUAAUUCCUGCUUUUUGAAGGUGUCUUGGCAUCUUCUGCCUUUGCUACUGAGCGGUUUCCUGAAACAGCCCUAAGCGUUCGCAAAGGCGCUUUGGUGCCUGCUGCGAGCACCUGUUUUCUGACUCGGAUGUUCCUUUAGAGGAAGGUGUUUUCCAGUGUCGGCCCUGAGAGGGCGUUCAGCAGGCGCGUCCUACCCACGCGGGGCUGAGGUCUCUCCUUCCAGGGAAGGUCCAUCCCGGCAGACGCCAGUGGCUUUGGCUCUGCAGCGCCAAGGAGGCGGCGUGGCGUCAUGCUCCGGGGAGCGCACAGGUUUCCUUCCAGUCGAACAAUUAACUUCAGAUCCAGCAGGUUUGACCCACCCUCACCUGCUGGGACAUGCGAGUGCUGGUGUCUGGAAGGAGGGCCGGGCUGUGCUGAGCUCUGGGGGGCCGGUCCCCACAGCUCCCCCGACAGGGCCCCCGGGGCCUCCUCUAUAAAUCAGGGGUCCGUGCUCCCAGCCCGCUUCGAGGGGUUUCUGCUUGGCGUGUGGGUUCUAAGUGCGAGCUGCUGUGUGUGGAGGCUCCUGAGCACCGGGUGCCCCUCGCGCGUGUGGGUCCCGGGGCAGCCCAGCUGCACACAGGAUGGUCCGGGGGUGCGGGUGGGGGCAGAGCUGAGCAUGGCGUGUACUUGGCCACAGAAGUCUUGCUGUGGUGCCGCUGGACCCCUGCUAGGAGGACAGGGUCCCCUCUCUCACGAAGCACACGGACCUCCAGAGUCCCUGCCCCUGCAGUCCUGGGAGCCUGCAGUUGGGGCUGGAGUUGGCCUCUCGGAGCCACCCAAACGGAGAGGCCCAUGAGAGGGGAGCUCAGGGGUCCAGCAGAGGCUGACAGAGUGGCCUCUUUGUCCUGUUGGCGGCCCCUGCUCAUGCCUGGGGCGUCCUCCCUGGAGCUGGGGGAGCUCAGGGACCCCCAGGUCUGUGUGGCUGCCCCUGCCACUCCAGGCACAGCGGCACGGCCCUCACUCUUUACCUAUUUGGAAUUGGAGGCAAUGAGUGGCAAGAACAUGAUGACAGACACGGGAGGUAAAAAUAUGUUCACUGGCUGUUCCCUUUAUAAAUAAGAAGUGGUGGGACUUGCGCUGCUAUUUUUAAAUAGACCAGAGAGUACACUGGAGAAGGCAUUGAGUGGUUUUAUUUUAAGUGGUGGAAAAAAUGAUGAGAAUCUCCUCCAGAUGACAGCUCCGGAAGUGUCGUGCCUGAACCCCUCUCACAGUCUGGCGGGCGCAGAGUCUGUGAGCGGCCAGGAGGCCACCUGCUCGACUGGCCCGUCCUCUCCAUGUGCCAGAUGCAGCCCAGCAUGACACUGCCCUCAGCUCAAAAACAGCACAGCUACUCUGUGUGCAGGAAAAAACUGCCAGUGACUUCACCAGGAUUUGAGAACGGUCCGUACGUUCACACUAAGCUGAGACAGCGCAGGUUAGAAGAUAGCGCGGGGAAGUAUUCACACUUCAGAUACGACCAUCACGGCCACAUGGCUAAGGCCCACACCCUCCCGGGGUGAAAUAACUACAGCAGAAGAAUGGGGCGCUAACCACCUCCACGGGCAUUUUAAAUAAAACCCAAAGUUGUUUUGUUUUUUUAAAAAAAAAAAAAAAGAAAGAAAGAAAGUGGCCGGGCACGGUGGCUCAUGCCUGUAAUCCCAGCACUUUGGGAGGCCGAGGCAGACAGAUCACGAGGUCAGGAGAUCAAGACCAUCCUGGCUAACACAGUGAAACCCUGUCUCUACUAAAAAUACAAAAAUUAGCCGGGCGUGGUGGUGGGUGCCUGUAGUCCCAGCUACUCGGGAGCCUGAGACAGGAGAAUGGCGUGAACCCGGGAGGUGGAGCUUGCAGUGAGCCGAGAUUGCGCCACUGCACUCCAGCCUGGGUGACAGAGCGAGACUCCGUCAAAAAAAAAAAAAAAAAGAAGAAAAGAAAAGAAAAGAAAACAGGAUAUUUAUUUUAGCUUCUUAGUUAACAUCAUUAAUUUUGUGUAGUUGAGCGACUCGUUGACUGCCUCCUCCCUGCAGUUUUUUACGGUGCCUCCGGCUGUCGACAGGCCCACUGUGAGCCGCAGGUCUGUGGGUGCAAGUGACAACAGCCGGGCGGGAGGCGGUGCACUCAGGCGGCAGGAAGGUCCCGAGACGGCGACGAGAAUGUGGUCAUGUUCAGGACACUCGCUCAGGGAGGGUCGUUGUCUGGGAUUUUACACGCUCAGCACCACCUCCUUAUUCUGUUCUCAGGGUAUCUCUGCUGUUGGAGUUACGGUCUUUCGGUUGUGUAUUAGGCUACAGCUAUUUAUUAAAUUUGUUCUUGUUCAUAUUCUUCUUUGUAUAUAAACAACCCUAAAAUGGGUUAGUCAGAAAAAAUUACUAAAUGUCAUUUGUUGUAUUCUCUCUGUAUUUUUACUAACAUCAUUCAGCUGGAAAUAAUUUCAAAAAGAAAUAAAAUACCUUUCCCAUUAC